GGAAGAGGAAGAAGAAGAAGAAGAAGAAGAAGAAGAAGAAGAAGAAGAAGAAGAAGAAGAAGAAGAAGAAGAAGAAGAAGAAGAAGAAGAAGAAGAGGAAGAAGAAGAAACUGUCUCUAGACCUUCAUUCUCAGGACAAGUUCAUUGUCUGGCACCAAGCUCCUUGGGGUGAAUUUUCUUCCAAAAGAGUCCGGGGAGUCCAGGUCCUUCAUCCUGGAUACUCAUAACGCGGCCCCAUUUCUCACUCCCAUUGGGCGUCGCGUUUCUAGAGAAGCCAAUCAGUGUCGCCGCAGUUCCCAGGUUCUAAAGUCCCACGCACCCCGCGGGACUCAUAUUUUUCCCAGACGCGGAGGUUGGGGUCAUGGCGCCCCGAAGCCUCCUCCUGCUGCUCUCAGGGGCCCUGGCCCUGACCGAUACUUGGGCGGGCUCCCACUCCUUGAGGUAUUUCAGCACCGCUGUGUCGCGGCCCGGCCGCGGGGAGCCCCGCUACAUCGCCGUGGAGUACGUAGACGACACGCAAUUCCUGCGGUUCGACAGCGACGCCGCGAUUCCGAGGAUGGAGCCGCGGGAGCCGUGGGUGGAGCAAGAGGGGCCGCAGUAUUGGGAGUGGACCACAGGGUACGCCAAGGCCAACGCACAGACUGACCGAGUGGCCCUGAGGAACCUGCUCCGCCGCUACAACCAGAGCGAGGCUGGGUCUCACACCCUCCAGGGAAUGAAUGGCUGCGACAUGGGGCCCGACGGACGCCUCCUCCGCGGGUAUCACCAGCACGCGUACGACGGCAAGGAUUACAUCUCCCUGAACGAGGACCUGCGCUCCUGGACCGCGGCGGACACCGUGGCUCAGAUCACCCAGCGCUUCUAUGAGGCAGAGGAAUAUGCAGAGGAGUUCAGGACCUACCUGGAGGGCGAGUGCCUGGAGUUGCUCCGCAGAUACUUGGAGAAUGGGAAGGAGACGCUACAGCGCGCAGAUCCUCCAAAGGCACACGUUGCCCACCACCCCAUCUCUGACCAUGAGGCCACCCUGAGGUGCUGGGCCCUGGGCUUCUACCCUGCGGAGAUCACGCUGACCUGGCAGCGGGAUGGGGAGGAACAGACCCAGGACACAGAGCUUGUGGAGACCAGGCCUGCAGGGGAUGGAACCUUCCAGAAGUGGGCCGCUGUGGUGGUGCCUUCUGGAGAGGAACAGAGAUACACAUGCCAUGUGCAGCACGAGGGGCUGCCCCAGCCCCUCAUCCUGAGAUGGGAGCAGUCUCCCCAGCCCACCAUCCCCAUCGUGGGCAUCGUUGCUGGCCUUGUUGUCCUUGGAGCUGUGGUCACUGGAGCUGUGGUCGCUGCUGUGAUGUGGAGGAAGAAGAGCUCAGGAAAGUUGACUCAUACUGGUGUCCAGUGAAGAAACCCAGGCGCAUAAGAGGGACAGUUGGAUCUCAGGUUUGUGCUUGAUCUGGAAAAGGAAGAGCAGAGACCACUAGGAGGCACCACUGCACUGCUCAUGAGCCCAGGAGGUGGAUGCCCAGGCUGAGCUCAGGGUGGAGAGAUGUCAUUGCUCAUCCUCCAGGUUCCAGGUGAAAACCCACCUGCCCAGCCCAUCUGCUUCUCCCUGGUUCUUCAAUUCUAGGGAGGACUGUCUUCUUCUCACCUCCCCGGACGAUGCUUCUUGACACAGGAAAGAGGAUGUGCUGCUAGGGUCAUCAUGUCCUGGUUUAUUGUGUUGUCAGUAGAAUGAAAUCAAAAUACAUACUCCAUAAAUAAUAAAAUAACCCAUAAUAAGUAAACAUUUACAAUUUACUCACACCAUUGAGGUUUCCUCCAGGUGUGAGCACAGCUGCAGACACACCUUGUCGCUUCAGUCAGGACACAGGACAGAGUAAAAUGGGAAGAAACCACAGUCACUGCAGAAAGGGCCCCCAUGGAAGAGGCCUGGCAGGGAGGCCAGCUGCCCCAGGGCCACCAUAUUUAGAGAUGACUUCCCCUUUCUAGGCAGGACUGGGAUUUUAAAAUUCUUUUUGUAUUCAUAGUUGUUCUGAAAUUGCAGGAUGAUGAGACCCAGCACUGGUGAGUUAUACUGUCUCUUUCUUCCCUAUUAAAUUCUGUGCCAAACAGCACCUUCAUAUAUUUAUCUCCUCUUCCUGGAGAGAAUAAAAACAAUGGAAAAAUUGAACCAUACAAACAUACUUUAAAUAUGUGCUGUCAGAAGUAGCUACUAAAGGAUUAAUUCCACCAAAGUGAGGGAAGGUUUGAAAAGAAAAACAUUGUAUACCCAUAUUCAAAGCAGCAUUAUUCACGAUAGCCAAGACAACACACACCAACACAUGAAUGAAGAAAAUGUGGUAUAUAUCGACAACGGAAUAUCAUUCAGCCUUAAGAAGGAAACCUGGUCACAGGCUGCAACAGGGAUGAACCUGAAGGACACUGCUAAGUAAAAUAAGCCAAUCACAAAGAAAACCCAAUACUGCACAUUUCCAUUUAUAUGAGGUGUCUAAACUGAAAGUAGACUAAUGGCUGCUAGGGGCUCGGUGAGGGGGAUGGAUGAAUGUUUGUUCAAUGGGCAUAGAGUUUCAGUGUUGCAAGAUGAAAAGUUCUAGAGAUCUGUUGCACAACUAUGUAUUUACAGUUAAUACUGUACUACUGUAUACUUUAAAAUAGUUAAGAUACCAAAUUUUACAUAAUGUAGUUUUUGGCCCAAGGAAAAGACUAAUUAGCCCUGUUACUAAUUUAGGGAAAAAGUACAUGAAUUCAUUAAAAAUAUAUUAGUAUGCGCUUACCUUAGAUACAGAAAACUAUGAGACAAAAAGAGAGAUCCCUGCUACCCCAGCUAUCACCCAUGAACCAGGAAAAUCAGCACCUCCUGAAACUAGACAGAAAGGCUCACAGGCCCAGCCUUGACAUGUUGAAUCAGUCUGCAUUUUGGCUGGAACCCAGGUGGCUCCACUGCAUGUAAAGCACCUUCCCAGAUAGUGAUGGAGGGAGAUCCUAGGACAGUGACUCUGCUCCACGGGGAGAAGCCUCCAAUCCAGAUGGGAGCAGCCAGAAGGGCCCAGGAGGGACAUUUCCAAGAAGAUAAAAUUAACAGAAUGUCCAAAGUGUCCAACGUCUUGAAAGAAUCAUACAAACAAAAGAGAUAUCAAACUUAAAUUAAUGAGAGUUAAUAAAAUAAACAAAAACAAAUACAAGUAUUAACUCCAAGAAGAACCAAUGUUGUACAGGCAGUGAAAAGUAGUCCAGUUGACAUAUGAGAGGAUUAGUCAUGGUAAAAGAAACAAGAGAUGGCUGAACUAAACAUAAUCACUAUAUAAAUAUACUGGGAAGAGUGAAAGAGAACAAGUACUCUUAACUGUUGCAUCCACCAUUGCGCUGUGCAACAAUGGGUGCAUCUGAAAAAAAUCAAGCAAUAAUAAUAAAGAAAUGGUAGUUAGAGAUACAGAAGUAAAGUCAAAAGAAUCAGCUAAAAAACUUGAAAGUGGUUGGCCCCUAGAAAGGCAGAAAUUGAGAAGAGGCAGAGAGGACUCUCAUUUUUCUCAAGAGAUUCUGCACAAAUAUUUGACUCUUUCAAUUAUGCACAAUUAUAAAUUUGAUUAAAAUAAAAACAAAAGCUUCAGUGAAUAUGCAAGUUUAUGUCUAAUGACAACCGCAUUCAACAAUGAUAUUUAAGGGUUAACUAAAAUGUGAAAAUACUUAAACAUGAAACAGGCAUGUAUAAAUGUGUUUUUGACACCAAACGUGAACACAAAUGUGAAAUAAUACACCUGUAAACACAUCUCUGGAUAGAUAGCCCACGAUUGAAUUCUCUACCCCACCUCCUUUACUGGUUGACCUGUGAACACAGGCAGGCAGUGGACCAGGACCCAACUAGGUUCCUUCAUCCUCUUGCUUCUAGGCAGGGCUUGCAUCCACUUUUGCUGCACAGAGGGCUCCCAUCCCUGCCUUGGUCCGUUUCACAGGUGAUCCCCUAACUCUCCCUGCCACCACUGCCUUACCUGAGUGGAGCUGAGGCUACCCUGACCAAGAAGAGCACCACCCAUCUGUGCCCCAAGGCCAGAAAGUUAAAAGGAACCUCACAACAGGGUCAGGAACUAUCCCACCUCCCCACUUACCAAUCAGUCUGAACUGAUAAUGGGAGAUGCUGAUACUUGCUUUACUCAUCCUCAUUCCCAGUUCAUUUAUUCUUCAUUAAUUCAGUCCAAUCUCCCCAGUGGUCACUUAACCCCAGAAGCAGACUGAUCUCUAUUCUUCUUAAUCAGGAAAGUCCAAAGCACUCCCUGUCCUCUCCCUCAUAUCAGACUUCAGCUCUGCAUCUGCAAGAUGCAGAGGUCCUCUGCAAGGCAGGUGUCUUCCCACAGGGUCAGCCCCUAAACACUGGCUGCAGAUGUCCCCCUCCAUCCCUUCCCAGCCCUUUCUGUGUUGCUGUGAAUCGUCCAUCACCGAGAACUGGUGGGGAGAUGCGGGGGAGGUGGGGAGAUUUCUUUGUGCUGUGUCAAGGCAUCAAGACAGACCUCUCCUUCUCUCUUGAACCUCAUACUCUAUCCCUUCCCAGACACUUGAAAUAAAACACAGACCAGAAAUGUCUA